GCACUGCUCUUCCCGGUCAUGGAGGCGCCAGCCGCCGGCUUGUUUCUGCUCCUGUUGCUUGGGACUUGGGCCCCGGCGCCGGGCAGCGCCUCCUCCGAGGCACCGCCGCUGAUCAAUGAGGACGUGAAGCGCACAGUGGACCUAAGCAGCCACCUGGCUAAGGUGACGGCCGAGGUGGUCCUGGCGCACCUGGGCGGCGGCUCCACGUCCCGAGCUACCUCUUUCCUGCUGGCUUUGGAGCCUGAGCUCGAGGCCCGGCUGGCGCACCUGGGCGUGCAGGUAAAGGGAGAAGAUGAGGAAGAGAACAAUUUGGAAGUACGUGAAACCAAAAUUAAGGGUAAAAGUGGGAGAUUCUUCACAGUCAAGCUCCCAGUUGCUCUUGAUCCUGGGGCCAAGAUUUCAGUCAUUGUGGAAACAGUCUACACCCAUGUGCUUCAUCCGUAUCCAACCCAGAUCACCCAGUCAGAGAAACAGUUUGUGGUGUUUGAGGGGAACCAUUAUUUCUACUCUCCCUAUCCAACGAAGACACAAACCAUGCGUGUGAAGCUUGCCUCUCGAAAUGUGGAGAGCUACACCAAGCUGGGGAACCCCACGCGCUCUGAGGACCUACUGGAUUAUGGGCCUUUCAGAGAUGUGCCUGCCUAUAGUCAGGAUACUUUUAAAGUACAUUAUGAGAACAACAGCCCUUUCCUGACCAUCACCAGCAUGACCCGAGUCAUUGAAGUCUCUCACUGGGGUAAUAUUGCUGUGGAAGAAAAUGUGGACUUAAAGCACACAGGAGCUGUGCUUAAGGGGCCUUUCUCACGCUAUGAUUACCAGAGACAGCCAGAUAGUGGAAUAUCCUCCAUCCGUUCUUUUAAGACCAUCCUUCCUGCUGCUGCCCAGGAUGUUUAUUACCGGGAUGAGAUUGGCAAUGUUUCUACCAGCCACCUCCUUAUUUUGGAUGACUCUGUAGAGAUGGAAAUCCGGCCUCGCUUCCCUCUCUUUGGCGGGUGGAAGACCCAUUACAUCGUUGGCUACAACCUCCCAAGCUAUGAGUACCUCUAUAAUUUGGGUGACCAGUAUGCACUGAAGAUGAGGUUUGUGGACCAUGUGUUUGAUGAACAAGUGAUAGAUUCUCUGACUGUGAAGAUCAUCCUGCCUGAAGGAGCCAAGAACAUUGAAAUUGAUAGUCCCUAUGAAAUCAGCCGUGCCCCAGAUGAGCUGCACUACACCUAUCUGGACACAUUUGGCCGCCCUGUGAUUGUUGCCUACAAGAAAAAUCUGGUAGAACAGCACAUUCAGGACAUUGUGGUCCACUACACGUUCAACAAGGUGCUCAUGCUGCAGGAGCCCCUGCUGGUGGUGGCGGCCUUCUACAUCCUGUUCUUCACCGUUAUCAUCUAUGUUCGGCUGGACUUCUCCAUCACCAAGGAUCCAGCCGCAGAAGCCAGGAUGAAGGUAGCCUGCAUCACAGAGCAGGUCUUGACCCUGGUCAACAAGAGAAUAGGCCUUUACCGUCACUUUGACGAGACCGUCAAUAGGUACAAGCAAUCCCGGGACAUCUCCACCCUCAACAGUGGCAAGAAGAGCCUGGAGACUGAACACAAGGCCUUGACCAGUGAGAUUGCACUGCUGCAGUCCAGGCUGAAGACAGAGGGCUCUGAUCUGUGCGACAGAGUGAGCGAAAUGCAGAAGCUGGAUGCACAGGUCAAGGAGCUGGUGCUGAAGUCGGCGGUGGAGGCUGAGCGCCUGGUGGCUGGCAAGCUCAAGAAAGACACGUACAUUGAGAAUGAGAAGCUCAUCUCAGGAAAGCGCCAGGAGCUGGUCACCAAGAUCGACCACAUCCUGGAUGCCCUGUAGCCCCUGCCCGCAUCCUCCAGGGGGCCCAGGGUGCCUGCACUUUGCUGUGGCAGGCAGAUUGGGUGGUAGUGGGAGGUUGUGCAUGGAGGCCAGUGAAAGCUGACAUCUGUAAAAGGCCUUCAAGGAAGAGAAACCAGGCCCUGCGUCAGGCAGUGUGAGUUUGCCGUUUGUCCUUAACUUUCUUUUUUUUUUUUUUUAAAAAAAGAAAACUUUAAAAAAACUCCCAUUAAAAACAAAACAUCUUUGUGUUUUGAACAAAGGAAUUUUCAAUAUUUGAUUGGUAUUCUGUUCUGAAGUCUAAGAUAUUUUUCAGCCUAUAAAGCCCCCUGUUUUAUGCCCUUCUAAUUCUGAUGUUUGGGUAUUGUGUGAGUGCAUGUGUUUUUUUUUUUUUUUUUAAAGCGUGUGUGAACAAAUGGAAAUAAAGCAGGGACUGUGAACAUUU